GGAAACAAUAGAGGCCGCGCGCACAGAGCGAGCUCUUGCAGCCUCCCCGCCCCUCCCGCAACGCUCGACCCCAGGAUUCCCCCGGCUCGCCUGCCCGCCAUGGCCGACAAGGAAGCAGCCUUCGACGACGCAGUGGAAGAACGAGUGAUCAACGAGGAAUACAAAAUAUGGAAAAAGAACACCCCUUUUCUUUAUGAUUUGGUGAUGACCCAUGCUCUGGAGUGGCCCAGCCUAACUGCCCAGUGGCUUCCAGAUGUAACCAGACCAGAAGGGAAAGAUUUCAGCAUUCAUCGACUUGUCCUGGGGACACACACAUCGGAUGAACAAAACCAUCUUGUUAUAGCCAGUGUGCAGCUCCCUAAUGAUGAUGCUCAGUUUGAUGCGUCACACUACGACAGUGAGAAAGGAGAAUUUGGAGGUUUUGGUUCAGUUAGUGGAAAAAUUGAAAUAGAAAUCAAGAUCAACCAUGAAGGAGAAGUAAACAGGGCCCGUUAUAUGCCCCAGAACCCUUGUAUCAUCGCAACAAAGACUCCUUCCAGUGAUGUUCUUGUUUUUGACUAUACAAAACAUCCUUCUAAACCAGAUCCUUCUGGAGAGUGCAACCCAGACUUGCGUCUCCGUGGACAUCAGAAGGAAGGCUAUGGGCUUUCUUGGAACCCAAAUCUCAGUGGGCACUUACUUAGUGCUUCAGAUGACCAUACCAUCUGCCUGUGGGACAUCAGUGCCGUUCCAAAGGAGGGAAAAGUGGUAGAUGCGAAGACCAUCUUUACAGGGCAUACGGCAGUAGUAGAAGAUGUUUCCUGGCAUCUACUCCAUGAGUCUCUGUUUGGGUCAGUUGCUGAUGAUCAGAAACUUAUGAUUUGGGAUACUCGUUCAAACAAUACUUCCAAACCAAGCCACUCAGUUGAUGCUCACACUGCUGAAGUGAACUGCCUUUCUUUCAAUCCUUAUAGUGAGUUCAUUCUUGCCACAGGAUCAGCUGACAAGACUGUUGCCUUGUGGGAUCUGAGAAAUCUGAAACUUAAGUUGCAUUCCUUUGAGUCACAUAAGGAUGAAAUAUUCCAGGUUCAGUGGUCACCUCACAAUGAGACUAUUUUAGCUUCCAGUGGUACUGAUCGCAGACUGAAUGUCUGGGAUUUAAGUAAAAUUGGAGAGGAACAAUCCCCAGAAGAUGCAGAAGACGGGCCACCAGAGUUGUUGUUUAUUCAUGGUGGUCAUACUGCCAAGAUAUCUGAUUUCUCCUGGAAUCCCAAUGAACCUUGGGUGAUUUGUUCUGUAUCAGAAGACAAUAUCAUGCAAGUGUGGCAAAUGGCAGAGAACAUUUAUAAUGAUGAAGACCCUGAAGGAAGCGUGGAUCCAGAAGGACAAGGGUCCUAGAUAUGUCUUUACUUGUUGUGAUUUUAGACUCCCCUUUUUUCUUCUCAACCCUGAGAGUGAUUUAACACUGGUUUUGAGACAGACUUUAUUCAGCUAUCCCUCUAUAUAAUAGGUACCACCGAUAAUGCUAUUAGCCCAAACCGUGGGUGUUUUCUAAAUAUUAAUAGGGGGGCUUGAUUCAACAAAGCCACAGACUUAACGUUGAAAUUUUCUUCAGGAAUUUUCUAGUAACCCAGGUCUAAAGUAGCUACAGAAAGGGGAAUAUUAUGUGUGAUUAUUUUUCUUCUUAUGCUAUAUCCCCAAGUUUUUCAGACUCAUUUAAGUAAAGGCUAGAGUGAGUAAGGAAUAGAGCCAAAUGAGGUAGGUGUCUGAGCCAUGAAGUAUAAAUACUGAAAGAUGUCACUUUUAUUCAGGAAAUAGGGGGAGAUUCAAGUCAUAUAGAUUCCUACUCGAAAAUCUUGACACCUGACUUUCCAGGAUGCACAUUUUCAUACGUAGACCAGUUUCCUCUUGGUUUCUUCAGUUAAGUCAAAACAACACGUUCCUCUUUCCCCAUAUAUUCAUAUAUUUUUGCUCGUUAGUGUAUUUCUUGAGCUGUUUUCAUGUUGUUUAUUUCCUGUCUGUGAAAUGGUGUUUUUUUUUUUGUUGUUGGUUUUUUUUUUUUUUUUUUUAACUUGGGACCACCAAGUUGUAAAGAUGUAUGUUUUUACCUGACAGUUAUACCACAGGUAGACUGUCAAGUUGAGAAGAGUGAAUCAAUAACUUGUAUUUGUUUUAAAAAUUAAAUUAAUCCUUGAUAAGAGUUGCUUUUUUUUUUUAGGAGUUAGUCCUUGACCACUAGUUUGAUGCCAUCUCCAUUUUGGGUGACCUGUUUCACCAGCAGGCCUGUUACUCUCCAUGACUAACUGUGUAAGUGCUUAAAAUGGAAUAAAUUGCUUUUCUACAUAACCCCAUGCUGAUGGGUUUUAUUUAGUAUAAAACAUCCAUCAAACACCAGUCUCUGGCUUCUAGAAGAGUCCUUCAGAUGACAGUUGUUGUCCAUGGUCUUUGACUAUCAAGAGCAGAAUUAAAUGUAAUAGUCCCAGAGCUGUAGAAAAGAACUUUACUCCUUCCCAGGGAAAGUGAAAGACAUAAAACACUGAAUCAGAGGUGGCACAGAUUAGUCUUUGAUAAGGUAACGUUUCUUUGAAGUCUAUCUGUAGAGAACUACAUGGACUUCCAAGAGUGUCAAAGGCAGUGUGGUAGAGAGAAUUUAAGGCAAGAUUUAAAUUUGGAAAAGGUGCUUGAACCUUUUCUCAGAGGUUUUAUUUCCCCAGUAUGUUUUUCACUGGGGCCUUUACUUAGGUUAGAAAUAAUAGGCUUUGAAGGCCUCUAUCACCAGAUGCAAUAACCAGAUAAAAUUCCUGUUUUUUCCCAAUCGCUUAGUUUUUUGUUGUUGUUGUUUUUUAACUGAGUAGAUCAUUCUGACCCAGAACUACUUUCAUGAGGUAAGAUCUUUGGGAAAAUCUGAAUAGCGUUAACCAUUAGAUUCAAAUCUCAAAUGGUUUCUUUUCAAGUCUAGUUGUUUUAGAGUAUAGUGAGAAAUACCUUGACACAAUUUUAAGAGUAAACUAUAUGGGUCAGCAUAUCCUUGAACAAAAAGUAGACUUUGUAAAAGUAUUCAUUUAAAUUCUAACACUCGUGGCACAAAAGAAUGGAAAUUGUAAACCCAUGUAAUGGAAAUUGGCUAUCUUUUUGACCCCACAUGUGCCCCUCAAAAAUGUUUUUGGUUUGGGUCAACACAAGGCAAGAUACAUUCUUUAAAAUACUCCCAGAUGUGUCCAUACAUUCAUCCUUCACUCAGUGCAUAUGUGAGGGUUGUUGCUGGAAGACAGGAGGCUCAUCUUUCCUUUCCUUGGUGCAUUGAGAUCAGUAUCAACAGCAGAUGAAAUAGAAUCCAGCAAAGAGUUGACAUGUUCUGCCUCCGGCCAACUCUAGAAUCUUUUUAAGCAGGUCAGCCAGUAUUUGCAACUUCCACAGGAUGAAUUGCUUGCCAAGUUUCUGGCACUCUUGUCUGGUUGGAAGAGUACAUCCAAAGGGUACUUAGUGAUCCUUUGCUAAGAAGUUUUUUGCUGUUUCCGGGUUACAGAUUUGGCCAUAUAUUUCUAAACAGCCCCUGUAAAGUUGAAAGAAAAAGUUUAUAACAGUGAACUUCUGAGGUUUAGUUACUGCAGGCUUUGUUGAGAAGAGAUUGUUACAGUGUGAUUUAUGGAUGAUCAGGGAUGACUUUCCCCUAGCAAAUAUUUGGAUGCCUCCUGUUUGUCAAAUAGAAUGAAUGGUGAUGGUGAUGGGAGGGAUAGUUAAACGUUUUCUCUGCUAGGUUAACUUCUUACAGGUAUAAUUACAAUGCCUGAAAUUCUGUAGUUUCAUUUCUUUGGAUUAGUCGUUGUCUUUUCCAGAUUGUACACAAUCUGAUCAACACAAAGGUAGUUAGUAGAUCAUUAACCUCAAUUGCAAGGUUAUAAUUUCUCAAACAUUAAGCAUAUUAUCAGUCAUGUGGAUUCAAACACAGUAUAAGAAAAUCCUCAAGGCUGGGUGUGAUGGCUUAUGCCUGUAAUCCCAGCUACUUAGCAGGCUGAGGCAGGAGUAUUGUUUGAACCCAGGAGGCAGAGUUGCAGUGAGCCAAGAUCGUGCCACUACUCCAGCCUGGGCAAAAUAGCAAGACCCGACCCCCCAUCUCUACUAAAAAGAAAUUUAAAAAAAUAAAAUCCUAGAAAAUUAGAAAAAGCAACAAUAGUUACUUGUGGGCCAGGCGCGGUGGUUCACGCCUGUAAUCCCAGCACUUUGAGAGGCUGAGGCACGUGGAUCACAAGGUCAGGAGUUCAAGACCAGCCUGGCCAAGAUGGUGAAACCCCGUUUCUACUAAAAAUACAAAAACUAGCUGGCCGUGGUGGCAUGCUCCUGUAGUCCCAGCUACUCAGGAGGCUGAGGCAGGAAAAUCACUUGAACCCAGGAGGUGGAGGUUGCAGUGAACUGAGACCGUGCCACUGCACUCCAGCCUGGGUGGCAGAGCGAGACUGUCUCAAAAAAAAAAGAAAGUUGUGAAUUUGAUGUAAGCUUAGGAAAUGAAUAAAAUUUAUAGGCAUCUGUAUAAUGUACAACUUGACACGGACUUUCUUUUAUCCUUAGUUUCUUUCACGGACUCUAGAACUUUUAUCAGAAUAUACUGGUAAAACAUUGGGGGAGGGAUCCUGAGUAGGUGAUUGGUCAGAAAGAUGCCUUCAGUUUUGUCAGUGUCUAAAAGUUAAGUCUGUUUAGGCCAAGCAUGGUGGCUCACACCUGAAAUCCCAGCACUCUGGGAGGCCGAGGCAAGUGGAUCACAAGGUCAGGAGAUGAGACCAUCUUAGCCAACAUGGUGAAACCCCGUCUCUACUAAAAUACAAAAAAAUUAGCCAGGCGUGGUGGUGCGUGCCUAUAAUCCCAGCUACUUGGGAGGCUGAGGCAGGGGAAUCGCUUGAACCCGGGAGGCAGAGGUCACGCCACUGCACUCCAGCCUGGCAACAGAGCAAGACUCCGUCUCAAAAAAAAAAAAAAAAAAAAAGAGUAAGUCUGUGUAACAUGAACAUCUCUGCUUCCACCCAAAACCACAGCCUUUGAAUAUUAUAUAAGGAACUUAAUGGAUAGAUAUGUUUAUUAUUUUUGAUAGCACAACUGCUUUCUCUGCUAUUAUAAGGAAAACUGAGAAUAGCAGGUGGGUAGGGUAGGAUGAGGAAACAAGAUGCCCAAAGCCUAGAUGCCACAGAAUUCAUGGUGAUAAUCAGGGCAUAUUUUGAGUCCUACUAGAAACAAACAUUCCAAAUGAACUCUGAAUGCCUGACUCAGGCGUUUUGGAGGUUUGGGUUAUCCCCUUGUCAUUAGGCACACAAGGGUUUUUUGUUGUUUUUGUUUUUUGGGUUUUUGUUUUGUUUUGAGGCAGUCUCACUCUGUUGUACAAGCUGGAGUGCUGUAUUGUGAUCUUGACUCACUGCAACCUCUGCCUCCUGGUUCAAGCGAUUCUCCUGCCUUGGCCUCCUGAGUAGCUGGGAUUAUAAGUGCCUGCCACUAUGCCCGGCUAAUUUUUGUAUUUUUAGUGGAGAUGGAGUUUUGCCAUGUUGGCCAGGCUGGUCUUGAACUCCUGACUCCAGGUGAUCCACCCUCCUCAGCCUCCCAAAGUGCUAGGAUUACAGGCGUGAGCCACCCCGUCCGGCCUGUUUUUAAGGCAUUAAUUAGUAUUGUUAGGAAAGCAGUAACAAUGCAAACACCACUCUUCUCUUCACAAAGAUCACCUUGAGACUGUGUCUCCAUUCCACCUGCCUGAGAAGUGGGAGCAUCAGCCUGUUCCAGGCUCUUGGGUAGUAGCAUAGCCCUUUAAAAAGAGAGAGCCAUUUUCCAUGUGUUUUUGGAUAAGCACAAUUUGAAAAUCAUUUCCCAAAUCCUCUUUUUGUUUUUGAUUCUAAGGUAAAAUUUUCCCUAAGCCCUCCCACCAUCCCCUCAGCCAGUAUUAGAUGAGAUUUGUAUAGCAGCAGAAACUGACUUAUAAGUAGAGAGCUCUUCAGCAAGACUGAGCCUUAGCUGUUCCAUCUCUUUGUUCUUCUGUUGCUGGAGUUGCACCCCAUUUCUUAACUGCCUCUGGCGUUCUUCCAUUUCCUCCAGCUGUUCCUGCAUGAGAUGGCCAAGAACAUUUCUAAUGAGCCAAACAAUAAAAACUCACAUUGUCCACUCUUACUUAUAAAACACUUUUUUGUUCAUUGUUUAAUCUUGAUAGCAGUAUUGAGGCUGGUAUUUAUAUGAUAGGUUAUGAAACAGGUUCAAAGAAGUUGUGUCUUGGAAAAAAAGUGACAAUGCUUUUGAAAAUGAUGACGAAAAAGGCAUCUUGUCUGUUAACCACAGCUUGCUUUAAUAGAAUCCUGGGAGGGUGAUUGGGACUUUUUAGUAUUACAACCUUAGUGUCAUUGAGGAGGAUUUUGGUCUAGUUAGUGGGCUGAGUUUCAUAUACCUCUCCCUCCAUGUGCAGGUUUGUUAAGAUAAUUGGUAGUUUUUAAUAAUAUAAAAUACUUAAGUUGAAAUACAAAAGUGUGGCAACAAUUAUUAAAUAUUGGCUAGAAUUCUAGGAGAGUUACACAACUAGUGGAAGUCCAUGUUUAGAAAAUAAAUGGCUUGUUUAAGGAAAAGUUUUUGUGUCCAAAGCUCCUUAAAGUCAGAGAGAUUUCUACCUGGUACUUAACAUCAUAUGGAAAUUGAUGCUUUAGUGAGGGUGUUGGCUAUCCUAUUGCUAAUUUCCUGCAUCCUUUUUUCUUCUUUAUUUUUGUAUAGAGACAGGGUCUCGCUAUGUUGCCCAGGCUGGUCUUGUUCCUGGGCUCAAGCAGUCCUCCCGCCUCGGUCUCCCAAAGUGCUGGGAUUACAGGUGUGAGCCACUGUGCCCAGCUUAUCCUUUUUUCAUUACACAAAAAGACUGAAUUUGGUUAGUUCUAAGUUGGAAGAUAAAGAUGGUAUGCACAGGAGGCCCUUGGGAGCCCUCAGAUAACUUUCUCAUUCUUCCAGAAUCAGGCUGGGAUGCAUUCUGUAAAUUUUCCCUGCCUAGGAUGUAUACCUGAGGAAUAAGGUAAGGAAGAUGUCAGCAAGUCAGUCUCUGGUUUACCUGCUAGCUGGCAUGGAUCCUUAAGGAAGCAGGAGGGAGUUGGGAAGAGAGGAAGGGGUGAAGUUGGUAUCUUUUAAAGCGAGAGUGAUUUUACCUCAGAUUUUGAAGAAUACUAAGGAAUCCAGUUGUUGGGGUACAUGCUAUUAUUAGAAGGAUCUAGAUAAUUUGUCCUCUGAGUCAUACUUGACAUUGUACCUGUGGCACAUCAAUCCGCACUGUUUGAUACUCUGGCUGAAUCUCAGCUUUCACCAACAUUGUCAAAGGACCUUUUUUAGUGCCCAGCCAUGCCUAAGAGUGUGUCAUCUGAAGAGGGAAGCAUCUGCAUACUGCUGUCCUGAUUGCUCAGUCCUCACUACCUACCAGACCCGUUGGUAAGGUACAAAAGUACAUGCUUGGAAAAGCAGUCUGCACCACCAGUGAUAAGCUGUGACAGAGUGGAACAGCCUCAAUGAAAUGAAGGAAGGAUUGCUACAGUGGCAUUAAGGAUGGUCUCUUAAUCCUGUGUUAACCACUAGAUUAACUUUACAAUCAACUCAAAAUCCUUCAAAGGCUUUCCACUUUCUUUAGUGGCAUUCAGACCCCCUCUAGUUUGACCCCUACCUCCAACUUGAACCUCUGUUACUCUUCCGUAUGAACAUUUUCCUCUAGCCCUGGACUACUAGUACCGAAGUCACUAGUCACAUAGGACUCAUUUGAAAUAUGACUAGUCUCAAUUGAGAUGUAAUGUAAGUGUAAAAUACACAGCAGAUUUCUAAGACAGCACACAAAAUGUAAAAUAUGUCAAAAAUAUUUGAUACUGAUUACAUGUUGAAAUAUAUGUGUUGGGUUAAAUAAAAUGCAUUAAAGUUAA